GCACCGGAAGCGGCUCCGAGGAAGGCCUGUGGGAGUCUCGGAGACGUGUCUGUCUGUGAGGCGCUGGGUGCACGUCCCCAGGGCUCUGGGCUAGGAAGGCAGCGGCGAGGUGCCUCCCCACGUACCCCUCGCGGGCCCAGCCGAGCAACGUGGGGCGAAGGCGGCGGCGAAGGCCCGGGCUGGGAGCGUUGGCGGCCGGAGUCCCAGCCAUGGCGGAGUCUGUGGAGCGCCUGCAGCAGCGGGUCCAGGAGCUGGAGCGGGAACUUGCCCAGGAGAGGAGUCUGCAGGUCCCGAGGAGCGGCGACGGAGGGGGCGGCCGGGUCCGCAUCGAGAAGAUGAGCUCAGAGGUGGUGGAUUCGAAUCCCUACAGGUAACCUGCGUCGCCGGUCGGAGGCAGGCGCGGGGGACGAGGUCAGGCUCCGUGAGGUCAGAAGUGAGGCGCUUCCCACGUCCCGCUCAUGGGGACGCCCGCCACCCUUUUCUUGGUCUGCGAAUCCUGUUCCCAAAUGGGCAAGGCCACAUCUUAGUACUGAUCGGAAGAUAUUCUUUCUCUUUUUUAAAAACCUCCAGUGAGUCAGCCAUAUGGUGCUGCUCCUGUGCCUGCUGAGGACGUGUGUCCAGUUUCCUAUCACCCUUGCCUCUUAAUUAGUCCGCCUCGCUGUGUAUAAGACUGAUAGUAAGAACUUUCAGAAGAUGAGAUCAAAUAUUAAACCUGCUAAGCCGCUUGAUGGCAUUGAAACGAAUGGGAAUUGUAAGCGACUAUGAGAAAAUCCGUACCUUUGCCGUAGCAAUAGUAGGUGUUGGUGGAGUAGGUAGUGUGACUGCUGAAAUGCUGACAAGAUGUGGCAUUGGUAAGUUGCUACUCUUUGAUUAUGACAAGGUGGAACUAGCCAAUAUGAAUAGACUUUUCUUCCAACCUCAUCAAGCAGGAUUAAGUAAAGUUCAAGCAGCAGAACAUACUCUGAGGAACAUUAAUCCUGAUGUUCUUUUUGAAGUACACAACUAUAAUAUAACCACAGUGGAAAACUUUCAACAUUUCAUGGAUAGAAUAAGUAAUGGUGGGUUAGAAGAAGGAAAACCUGUUGAUCUAGUUCUUAGCUGUGUGGACAAUUUUGAAGCUCGAAUGACAAUAAAUACAGCUUGUAAUGAACUUGGACAAACAUGGAUGGAAUCUGGGGUCAGUGAAAAUGCAGUUUCAGGGCAUAUACAGCUUAUAAUUCCUGGAGAAUCUGCUUGUUUUGCGUGUGCUCCACCACUUGUAGUUGCUGCAAAUAUUGAUGAAAAGACUCUGAAACGAGAAGGUGUUUGUGCAGCCAGUCUUCCUACCACUAUGGGUGUGGUUGCUGGGAUCUUAGUACAAAACGUGUUAAAGUUUCUGUUAAAUUUUGGUACUGUUAGUUUUUACCUUGGAUACAAUGCAAUGCAGGAUUUUUUUCCUACUAUGUCCAUGAAGCCAAAUCCUCAGUGUGAUGACAGAAAUUGCAGGAAGCAGCAGGAGGAAUAUAAGAAAAAGGUAGCAGCACUGCCUAAACAAGAGGUUAUACAAGAAGAGGAAGAGAUAAUCCAUGAAGAUAAUGAAUGGGGUAUUGAGCUGGUAUCUGAGGUUUCAGAAGAGGAACUGAAAAAUUUUUCAGGUCCAGUUCCAGACUUACCUGAAGGAAUUACAGUGGCAUACACAAUUCCAAAAAAGCAAGAAGAUUCUGUCACUGAGUUAACAGUGGAAGAUUCUGGUGAAAGCUUGGAAGACCUCAUGGCCAAAAUGAAGAAUAUGUAGAUAAUGGACUGGGAUAUAUUGUAUUUCUCAUGUUAAAGCCUCUUCCCUUGAAAUUAAAAAAAAAUUUUAACUGAUAAAACUUAGGGCAACAUUAAUUAAUGUAUAUUCUUACCUGAAUUGUUAUACUUUUUGAAAAUCCUGUGACUUGCCUGUUUCUCCCCGCUCCAACGAAAUCAUUAACUCUCCUAAAAUGUGUUUCAUUCUAGUAAGAAAACCUCAAAGGAUAUUGUAGGAUAUAAAUCUUACUUGAAAACAUAGCUGUUGAAAUGUUUUGGCCUUUUGGAGUGGGGGAAGGACAAAUCUGAUCCUGUAAUCUUUUUCUUUCCAGUAAUCCCUUGUGUCUGUUGCAUGAGGACAUGGACAAUAAAGUAGUAUAUGAUCCUCAGAUACAGGGAGAAGGACAAGGCAUACAGCUUAUUGAUUAGAGCUGGCAAGCAUCUGCUCAUUAUGUUUGGAAUUGCUUUCUAUAAGAAAAUUGCCCACUACUACUAACUUGAUCAACAAUGAAUUCAAAAUAGUUAACCUAUGAAAUAACAUCCUCUCAAAUGUUUGCUGAUGAAGUACAAGUUGAAAUGUAGUUAUUGGAAAAGUCUGUAACCUGUGGAUCAUAUAUAUUCAAAGUGAGACAAAGGCAAAUAAAAAGCAGCUAUUUUCAUGAAUAGACAAAGUUGAUUUCAGGAAGUAUAAAUUAUAUUCUGCACCGAACAAGGAACAGAAAUUAUUGCAUCUGUGGAACAUAUAUCUGGAGUUACUAUACUUUACUGAAGAGCAAGGCAUAAAUUUAGACUAAAAUCCAUCCAGAUUACACUCAUUCUUUAGGCUACUCCUGGAUACUUCAUUUAAAUUUGAUUUUCGAGGUAGUGAGAUGUCGGCAAGGUUUGUCCUGUAUAUUAGGAAUAAAGGAAAAGUUCUAAACUGCCUCUGCAAUGACUUGUAGUCAGUGGAAGAGUAUCACUUUCCCCUGAUCAUGACCACUAAACUGUAAAUUGAUAUAAAUUAGUUUUCUCUCGAGUUACACCCAAGUAAUGAAGACUUAAGAGAACCUUGGUUGAAAUAAAUUUCCAAUAGUUUGGAGACUCAUAAAUACCAUGCAGGUGUAACCACUGCCAAUAGGCUGUUUCUAUGCUUAUUUCCUAUUUUGAUUUUUACUUUGAAGAUAGGAAUAUCUAAAUUAUAUCUCUAGGGAGAAAAUGUUGUAAAAAAUUAAAAGUACAUCCCUGAUUGUAAAAUAAAGUUCAAAAAACUGAUUUCAGAAAGUCUCAACUACCAAAUGUUUUCAAUAUAUUAGUUUUGAGAUGCUAGGAUUAUACUGUGAUUCUUAUGUUUAUAGUAAAGUCUGGAAAGCAGAAGGAUAGUUUUUUUAGCCUGGAAACUUAUUUAUGUUGCCUUGGUGAGUCUUCUAUCAUUUUUUAAAAAUUUAGCUUAUUGAACUGUAAAAUAGCUUUUCUAGUAUGAGAGAUGUUUUGAAUUUAAAAAAUGAAAUGCAGUUUUUCAAAAAUAAAUUUCCUUUGGAAAUUCUUGCAUAUCAAUUUAGUAAGGUUUUAUAAAAUUUUACAAUUUGAUAAAGUAUCACAUCUAGAAUUCACUGUCUUCUUUUAUCUGCUCUCAAGUUGGCAUUGCAUCACUGCCUGUGUCUUACACUGCACCAAAUGUUACCUAAUUGACCUAACUUUUUUUGUCUAAUAUCUUUCAUUAAAAACAAUUGGAUUAUUUAACCAGAAAAAAAAUCUGGUAAUAGAGAUGUUGCUAUCCUAGAAUACUCUCUUGACAGUCUGUAUGCCAUGAAAACUUGCAUAAGAAGGCAGCUGAUUACGAAAAAUUAAUCAUCAUUGAAUUUAGUAUUACUAAACUCAUAGCAUUUGUCCAGAUUUGUAAACACUAUUGAUUCUAAUGUGAAAGAUGGAAAAGCAGUCCCAGAAUUGGCUUAGCACAGAGACUCUAAAUGAUAGUAAAACAACAUAUUCAACUUUAAUUCCUGUCUUAUUGUUAAUGGGAAGUUAGUUAUGGUUCUACUUAAAUGUUGUAGAGAAAAUAAGUAUUACUAGUUUCUUCUCAUAAAAAUACUCCCUGGAUACGUACACUGAACAACACAAAAAACGUAAUGGCCACUUAAGAAUAUUUAUUUAUUUAUUUAUUUUUUUGAGACAGAGUCUCACUCUGUUGCCCAGGCUGGAGUGCAGUGGCACGAUCUCAGCUCACCACAUCCUCCGCCUCCCAGGUUCAAGCGAUUCUCCUGCCUCAGCCUCCCAAGUAGCUGGGAUUACAGGUGCCCGCCACCACGCAUGGCUAAUUUUUGUAUUUUUAGUAGAGGCGAGGUUUCACCAUGUUGGCCAGGCUGGUCUUGAACUCCUGACCUCAGGUGAUCCACCCAUCUUGGCCUCCCAAAGUGCUGGGAUUAUAGGUGUGAGCCACCACGCCCAGCCAAGAAUAUUUACUAAAGGAAGCUUUGACCCCUGCAUCACAUUUUUUUCAUAUUUCCCUUUCUGUAAUCUCAGCACUUUGGGAGGCUGAGGUGGGUAGGUCAAGAGGUCAGGAGUUCGAGACCAGCCUGACCAACAUGGCAAAACCCCGUCUCUACUAAAAAUACAAAAAUUAGCCGGGCGUGGUGGUGCGUGACUGUAAUCCCAGCUACUUAGGAGGCUGAGGCAGGAGAAUCGCUUGAACCUGGGAGGCAGAGGUUGCAGUGAGCUGAGAUAGUGCCACUGCACUCCAGUCUGGAAAACAGAGUGAGACUCUGUCUCAAAAAAAAAGGUAUUGAUGAAUAAAAAUUAUAACUAGAAUAAGUACUCUAACAAUUCAGAUUUAUAAUUGAGUUGUCUGAAAGCUACCUUUUUCAUUGUGAAAGUGCAUAUUAAUGUGAAGAAAAUAUUCCUAUUUGAGAACUUCAAAUAUGCAUACACAAAGAUGUUCCAGCUAUUUUUAUCUUCUUAAGUAUGCAUUCUACAUGAGAACGUUUGGGUUGGUAGUAAAAUAAAUAGUAAUAUCAAAAUAGUUUAUUAUGUUUAAAUUUCAUUCUUUUGGAAUACAUAAUUUUGAGUGAUCAUGUCUCCAACUACAGUUAUUCAGGCACAAAUUUUGGAGGUACAAAGAAUAAAUAAUAUUCUUAAGGUAGUUUUUCCUUUUAUCAGGGUUCUUCUAGAGUACUGGUCUCAUUAUUUUCUAAAGCAGUUUUUCUAAGGUGAUAAACCGAACACAUUACUUGCUAUGUAUUAAAUGACUUGUACCACUAAAUAAUCAAAUUCUAAGCUCUAACAGCUUAAUUCUAAAA